AGAGUGCCCUGGCAGCUGUCGGCUGGAAGGAACUGGUCUGCUCACACUUGCUGGCUUGCGCAUCAGGACUGGCUUUAUCUCCUGACUCACGGUGCAAAGGUGCACUCUGCGAACGUUAAGUCCGUCCCCAGCGCUUGGAAUCCUACGGCCCCCACAGCCGGAUCCCCUCAGCCUUCCAGGUCCUCAACUCCCGUGGACGCUGAACAAUGGCCUCCAUGGGGCUACAGGUAAUGGGCAUCGCGCUGGCCGUCCUGGGCUGGCUGGCCGUCAUGCUGUGCUGCGCGCUGCCCAUGUGGCGCGUGACGGCCUUCAUCGGCAGCAACAUUGUCACCUCGCAGACCAUCUGGGAGGGCCUAUGGAUGAACUGCGUGGUGCAGAGCACCGGCCAGAUGCAGUGCAAGGUGUACGACUCGCUGCUGGCACUGCCGCAGGACCUGCAGGCGGCCCGCGCCCUCGUCAUCAUCAGCAUCAUCGUGGCUGCUCUGGGCGUGCUGCUGUCCGUGGUGGGGGGCAAGUGUACCAACUGCCUGGAGGAUGAAAGCGCCAAGGCCAAGACCAUGAUCGUGGCGGGCGUGGUGUUCCUGUUGGCCGGCCUUAUGGUGAUAGUGCCGGUGUCCUGGACGGCCCACAACAUCAUCCAAGACUUCUACAAUCCGCUGGUGGCCUCCGGGCAGAAGCGGGAGAUGGGUGCCUCGCUCUACGUCGGCUGGGCCGCCUCCGGCCUGCUGCUCCUUGGCGGGGGGCUGCUUUGCUGCAACUGUCCACCCCGCACAGACAAGCCUUACUCCGCCAAGUAUUCUGCUGCCCGCUCUGCUGCUGCCAGCAACUACGUGUAAGGUGCCACGGCUCCACUCUGUUCCUCUCUGCUUUGUUCUUCCCUGGACUGAGCUCAGCGCAGGCUGUGACCCCAGGAGGGCCCUGCCACGGGCCACUGGCUGCUGGGGACUGGGGACUGGGCAGAGACUGAGCCAGGCAGGAAGGCAGCAGCCUUCAGCCUCUCUGGCCCACUCGGACAACUUCCCAAGGCCGCCUCCUGCUAGCAAGAACAGAGUCCACCCUCCUCUGGAUAUUGGGGAGGGACGGAAGUGACAGGGUGUGGUGGUGGAGUGGGGAGCUGGCUUCUGCUGGCCAGGAUAGCUUAACCCUGACUUUGGGAUCUGCCUGCAUCGGCGUUGGCCACUGUCCCCAUUUACAUUUUCCCCACUCUGUCUGCCUGCAUCUCCUCUGUUCCGGGUAGGCCUUGAUAUCACCUCUGGGACUGUGCCUUGCUCACCGAAACCCGCGCCCAGGAGUAUGGCUGAGGCCUUGCCCACCCACCUGCCUGGGAAGUGCAGAGUGGAUGGACGGGUUUAGAGGGGAGGGGCGAAGGUGCUGUAAACAGGUUUGGGCAGUGGUGGGGGAGGGGGCCAGAGAGGCGGCUCAGGUUGCCCAGCUCUGUGGCCUCAGGACUCUCUGCCUCACCCGCUUCAGCCCAGGGCCCCUGGAGACUGAUCCCCUCUGAGUCCUCUGCCCCUUCCAAGGACACUAAUGAGCCUGGGAGGGUGGCAGGGAGGAGGGGACAGCUUCACCCUUGGAAGUCCUGGGGUUUUUCCUCUUCCUUCUUUGUGGUUUCUGUUUUGUAAUUUAAGAAGAGCUAUUCAUCACUGUAAUUAUUAUUAUUUUCUACAAUAAAUGGGACCUGUGCACAGGAGGAAA